UGCAGAGCACAGAGAAAGGACAUCUGCGAGGAAAGUUCCCUGAUGGCUGUCAACAAAGUGCCACGUCUCUAUGGCUGUGAACGCUGAGCACACGAUUUUAUCGCGCCUAUCAUAUCUUGGUGCAUAAACGCACCUCACCUCGGUCAACCCUUGCUCCGUCUUAUGAGACAGGCUUUAUUAUCCGCAUUUUAUAUGAGGGGAAACUGACGGUGGAGAGAGAAUUAUCUUGCUCAAGGCGACACAGCAGAGCCCACAGGUGGCAGAAUCCCACCCGAGCCCGCUUCGACCCGCGGGGUGGAAACCACGGGCGCCCGCCCGGCUGCGCUUCCAGAGCUGAACUGAGAAGCGAGUCCUCUCCGCCCUGCGGCCACCGCCCAGCCCCGACCCCCGCCCCGGCCCGAUCCUCACUCGCCGCCAGCUCCCCGCGCCCACCCCGGAGUUGGUGGCGCAGAGGCGGGAGGCGGAGGCGGGAGGGCGGGCGCUGGCACCGGGAACGCCCGAGCGCCGGCAGAGAGCGCGGAGAGCGCGACACGUGCGGCCCAGAGCACCGGGGCCACCCGGUCCCCGCAGGCCCGGGACCGCGCCCGCUGGCAGGCGACACGUGGUCACGGUGAUCCAUUUGUAAAGUCGGGAAUAAAUGACCUCUGAAGUGUUGUCUGUAUAUUGAUCUGCUACCAGUAAAACAUAUCUCUAAUACGGAGUUCUAUACCAGAGUUGAUUGUUGAUGGCACAUACUUUUAGAGGAUGCUCAUUGGCAUUUAUGUUUAUAAUCACGUGGCUGUUGAUUAAAGCAAAAAUAGAUGCGUGCAAGAGAGGCGAUGUGACUGUGAAGCCUUCCCAUGUAAUUUUACUUGGAUCCACUGUCAAUAUUACAUGCUCUUUGAAGCCCAGACAAGGCUGCUUUCACUAUUCCAGACGUAACAAGUUAAUCCUGUACAAGUUUGACAGAAGAAUCAAUUUUCACCAUGGCCACUCCCUCAAUUCUCAAGUCACAGGUCUUCCCCUUGGUACAACCUUGUUUGUCUGCAAACUGGCCUGUAUCAAUAGUGAUGAAAUUCAAAUAUGUGGAGCAGAGAUCUUCGUUGGUGUUGCUCCAGAACAGCCUCAAAAUUUAUCCUGCAUACAGAAGGGAGAACAGGGGACUGUGGCCUGCACCUGGGAAAGAGGACGAGACACCCACUUAUACACUGAGUAUACUCUACAGCUAAGUGGACCAAAAAAUUUAACCUGGCAGAAGCAAUGUAAAGACAUUUAUUGUGACUAUUUGGACUUUGGAAUCAACCUCACCCCUGAAUCACCUGAAUCCAAUUUCACAGCCAAGGUUACUGCUGUCAAUAGUCUUGGAAGCUCCUCUUCACUUCCAUCCACAUUCACAUUCUUGGACAUAGUGAGGCCUCUUCCUCCGUGGGACAUUAGAAUCAAAUUUCAAAAGGCUUCUGUGAGCAGAUGUACCCUUUAUUGGAGAGAUGAGGGACUGGUACUGCUUAAUCGACUCAGAUAUCGGCCCAGUAACAGCAGGCUCUGGAAUAUGGUUAAUGUUACAAAGGCCAAAGGAAGACAUGAUUUGCUGGAUCUGAAACCAUUUACAGAAUAUGAAUUUCAGAUUUCCUCUAAGCUACAUCUUUAUAAGGGAAGUUGGAGUGAUUGGAGUGAAUCAUUGAGAGCACAAACACCAGAAGAAGAGCCUACUGGGAUGUUAGAUGUCUGGUACAUGAAACGGCACAUUGACUACAGUAGACAACAGAUUUCUCUUUUCUGGAAGAAUCUGAGUGUCUCAGAGGCAAGAGGAAAAAUUCUCCACUAUCAGGUGACCUUGCAGGAGCUGACAGGAGGGAAAGCCAUGACACAGAACAUCACAGGACACACCUCCUGGACCACAGUCAUUCCUAGAACCGGAAAUUGGGCUGUGGCUGUGUCUGCAGCAAAUUCAAAAGGCAGUUCUCUGCCCACUCGUAUUAACAUAAUGAACCUGUGUGAGGCAGGGUUGCUGGCUCCUCGCCAGGUCUCUGCAAACUCAGAGGGCAUGGACAACAUUCUGGUGACUUGGCAGCCUCCCAGGAAAGAUCCCUCUGCUGUUCAGGAGUACGUGGUGGAAUGGAGAGAGCUCCAUCCAGGGGGUGACACACAGGUCCCUCUAAACUGGCUACGGAGUCGACCCUACAAUGUGUCUGCUCUGAUUUCAGAGAACAUAAAAUCCUACAUCUGUUAUGAAAUCCGUGUGUAUGCACUCUCAGGGGAUCAAGGAGGAUGCAGCUCCAUCCUGGGUAACUCUAAGCACAAAGCACCACUGAGUGGCCCCCACAUUAAUGCCAUCACAGAGGAAAAGGGGAGCAUUUUAAUUUCAUGGAACAGCAUUCCAGUCCAGGAGCAAAUGGGCUGCCUCCUCCAUUAUAGGAUAUACUGGAAGGAACGGGACUCCAACUCCCAGCCUCAGCUCUGUGAAAUUCCCUACAGAGUCUCCCAAAAUUCACAUCCAAUAAACAGCCUGCAGCCCCGAGUGACAUAUGUCCUGUGGAUGACAGCUCUGACAGCUGCUGGUGAAAGUUCCCACGGAAAUGAGAGGGAAUUUUGUCUGCAAGGUAAAGCCAAUUGGAUGGCGUUUGUGGCACCAAGCAUUUGCAUUGCUAUCAUCAUGGUGGGCAUUUUCUCAACGCAUUACUUCCAGCAAAAGGUGUUUGUUCUCCUAGCAGCCCUCAGACCUCAGUGGUGUAGCAGAGAAAUUCCAGAUCCAGCAAAUAGCACUUGCGCUAAGAAAUAUCCCAUUGCAGAGGAGAAGACACAGCUGCCCUUGGACAGGCUCCUGAUAGACUGGCCCACGCCUGAAGAUCCUGAACCGCUGGUCAUCAGUGAAGUCCUUCAUCAAGUGACCCCAGUUUUCAGACAUCCCCCCUGCUCCAACUGGCCACAAAGGGAAAAAGGAAUCCAAGGUCAUCAGGCCUCUGAGAAAGACAUGAUGCACAGUGCCUCAAGCCCACCACCUCCAAGAGCUCUCCAAGCUGAGAGCAGACAACUGGUGGAUCUGUACAAGGUGCUGGAGAGCAGGGGCUCCGACCCAAAGCCCGAAAACCCAGCCUGUCCCUGGACGGUGCUCCCAGCAGGUGACCUUCCCACCCAUGAUGGCUACUUACCCUCCAACAUAGAUGACCUCCCCUCACAUGAGGCACCUCUCGCUGACUCUCUGGAAGAACUGGAGCCUCAGCACAUCUCCCUUUCUGUUUUCCCCUCAAGUUCUCUUCACCCACUCACCUUCUCCUGUGGUGAUAAGCUGACUCUGGAUCAGUUAAAGAUGAGGUGUGACUCCCUCAUGCUCUGAGUGGUGAGGCUUCAAGCCUUAAAGUCAGUGUGCCCUCAACCAGCACAGCCUGCCCCAAUUCCCCCAGCCCCUGCUCCAGCAGCUGUCAUCUCUGGGUGCCACCAUCGGUCUGGCUGCAGCUAGAGGACAGGCAAGCCAGCUCUGGGGGAGUCUUAGGAACUGGGAGUUGGUCUUCACUCAGAUGCCUCAUCUUGCCUUUCCCAGGGCCUUAAAAUUACAUCCUUCACUGUGUGGACCUAGAGACUCCAACUUGAAUUCCUAGUAACUUUCUUGGUAUGCUGGCCAGAAAGGGAAAUGAGGAGGAGAGUAGAAACCACAGCUCUUAGUAGUAAUGGCAUACAGUCUAGAGGACCAUUCAUGCAAUGACUAUUUCUAAAGCACCUGCUACACAGCAGGCUGUACACAGCAGAUCAGUACUGUUCAACAGAACUUCCUGAGAUGAUGGAAAUGUUCUACCUCUGCACUCACUGUCCAGUACAUUAGACACUAGGCACAUUGGCUGUUAAUCACUUGGAAUGUGUUUAGCUUGACUGAGGAAUUAAAUUUUGAUUGUAAAUUUAAAUCGCCACACAUGGCUAGUGGCUACUGUAUUGGAGUGCACAGCUCUAGAUGGCUCCUAGAUUAUUGAGAGCCUUCAAAACAAAUCAACCUAGUUCUAUAGAUGAAGACAUAAAAGACACUGGUAAACACCAAGGUAAAAGGGCCCCCAAGGUGGUCAUGACUGGUCUCAUUUGCAGAAGUCUAAGAAUGUACCUUUUUCUGGCCGGGCGUGGUAGCUCAUGCCUGUAAUCCCAGCACUUUGGGAGGCUGAGGCAGGCGGAUCAUGAGGUCAGGAGAUCGAGACCAUUCUGGCUAACAUGGUGAAACCCCAUCUCUACUAAAAAUAUUUUUAAAAAAAAUUAACUGGGCGUGAUGGCGGGCGCCUGUAGUCCCAGCUACUCGGGAGGCUGAGGGAGGAGAAUGACAUGAACCUGGGAGGUGGGGCUUGCAGUGAGCCACUGCACUCCAGCCUGGGCAACAGAGCAAGACUCUGUCUCAAAAAAGAAAAAAAAAAAAAAGAAUGUACCUUUUUCCUAGAUUUGCUGGUUUAUUGUUUUAUUUUGGCUUCAUCCUCUUUCAGCAAAUCAAGGGCAGCUGGAUGGUGAAGACCUAUAUUGUAAACUCACCAUAGUACCAUAGUACCUUGGGCAACCCAGCCUCCCACUCUGAAUCUCGGGUGUCUUGUAAAGGGCUGGACCAAAGGCUCCCUGACCCCUUGUUUCCUCUCCUUUUUGCUGCAGCAGGCCCUGCCUUCAGGACCAGGGCUGUCUCAGGGUCUAAGACCCCAACCUCUGAGGUUGUCCUCAGAAGUGGUCUGUCCCCUGUUCCCAAAGGCACAGCUUUCAUUCCCGGAGAAGAUAUUGAGCUGGUCCUCUGCCAGCUCAAGUUGAGCCUGGAAGAUAACUCUCUUUUCCACAACAUGGACUUGGAACAUGAUCCAUGUUUUGCUCUUUAAAGCUGUGGCCCCUGGCUUGCCACCCUCCCUAGCCCAUUGCUGCCUCUGUCUCUUCACCAUAGGCACUUCUGCCAAACUAGUGGAGAAGUCUUGGUCUAAACUGCUAAUAAUGCUCUUCCCUAAAGAACAGGAUAAAAGAUCCAAAAUACUUUUUCUUAAAUUCCUGUCAAGCCUGGGGUCCACCCCGUACCCCUUCCCACAUGAACGCUGGAACUGAGAUGGCUUCCCCAUCAUCGUCUGGAUUUUCAUUUAACAAAGUACUUGUUGUAAAUGUGUACUUCUUGCCUAACGUGAGGAACUAAAAACUUGUCCAUGCAUACCCCAGUCCUGUAGAAAUAACUGUUCUCGGGCUUUAGGUUUUCCAGAUUUCCCUCAGAGCUCUAGAAACUGAGCGAUGGACAGUUGCUCUGCUUCUUCAGGUUGGAACUCUUGAUACAUCCUUGUUUCCUGAAAUUCCAAACUUAACACCUAUAGUUCUCUCAGGCUUUUUUUGAAAAGUUCCUUCGUUUCUAUUUCUAUUCCACUCUAUUUAGCUAUUAUUGUGCGGCACCCCCAAUGGUUCCUUUCCUCUCAGCAUCGCUGUAGCUUGCCUGUACCCAGGACAUGCCCUUGACUGGCACAAACCGUGACAGACAUGCCCUUGACUGGCACAAACCAUGACAGACAAGGCCACCUCCUCAGAAGCGGAACAACCUAUUAUCUUUUGGCAAUGGGAGCUAACUUCACUGUUUUCUUACAAUACCUGGUUUUUCCUAUCUUUGGUUUCCUUUUGAUUAUCUCUCAUCCAUCUCAGCCACUAUUCUCCUCCCCUCCCUUGUGUCUACAACACCCCAUUUUACCAAGUCUCCCAUUUAACCUCCCCAUCCUUUUCUUUCCCUUAAAGUCUCAUAUGAUACUGCAGUCCUCAUUUGUCUUCCCAAAAAAAAAAAAGAAUUUUUUUUUUUUUAAGGAAUCCUUCCUUGACUCCUAAAGACUCCUAAGGAUGCUGAGGCCUCCUCAGCAUGAUUUCCAUAUACUUACUUUCUCUGUUGGACUGCAGACAACUUGAAAGCAGGAACUUUGGCAGUGUUUCCCCAGCACCAGCAUCAUGCCUGGUCCAUAGUAGCUACCAAUAAAAAAGUAAGCAUCAUGAACCCAAAA